GGGAAACGGAAGAUGGCGGCGGCGGCCGGGCACGGGGUUCCGGGCUCCGCUCGGGCAGAGCCCACCCGCUGACCAACGCCGCCGCCCCCGCCGGGCGGUGCUGUGUCCCCGCAGGAGUCGGAGAGGAUGGCAGGGGCCGGAGGCCAGCACCACCCUCCGGGCGCCGCUGGAGGAGCGGCCGCCGGAGCCGGCGCCGCGGUCACCUCCGCCGCUGCCUCGGCGGGGCCGGGAGAGGAUUCGUCUGACAGCGAAGCGGAGCAAGAGGGACCCCAGAAACUGAUCCGCAAAGUGUCUACCUCGGGGCAGAUCCGGACCAAGACCAGUAUUAAAGAGGGACAGCUAUUGAAGCAAACCAGUUCUUUCCAAAGGUGGAAAAAGCGAUACUUCAAACUUCGAGGCCGCACCCUUUACUAUGCAAAGGACUCAAAGUCUCUGAUAUUUGAUGAAGUUGACCUCUCAGAUGCUAGUGUAGCUGAAGCAAGCACGAAAAAUGCUAACAACAGCUUCACGAUCAUCACUCCAUUCAGAAGGCUAAUGCUGUGUGCUGAGAACAGAAAGGAGAUGGAGGAUUGGAUCAGCUCACUGAAGUCUGUACAGACCAGAGAACCCUACGAGGUGGCCCAGUUUAAUGUGGAACAUUUCUCAGGGAUGCACAACUGGUACGCCUGCUCCCACGCCCGACCCACCUUCUGUAACGUGUGCAGAGAGAGUCUUUCUGGAGUCACCUCCCAUGGCCUGUCCUGCGAAGUGUGUAAAUUCAAGGCUCACAAAAGAUGUGCAGUGAGAGCAACAAAUAACUGUAAAUGGACUACCCUGGCCUCCAUCGGGAAGGACAUUAUAGAAGAUGAAGAUGGCGUCGCGAUGCCUCACCAGUGGCUUGAGGGCAACCUGCCUGUAAGUGCCAAGUGUGCUGUCUGCGACAAAACAUGUGGCAGUGUUCUCCGUCUACAGGAUUGGAAAUGCCUUUGGUGUAAGACAAUGGUACACACUGCCUGCAAAGAUUUAUACCAUCCAAUAUGUCCACUUGGUCAAUGUAAAGUAUCUAUCAUACCUCCAAUUGCACUAAACAGCACCGAUUCCGAUGGUUUCUGUAGAGCAACAUUUUCGUUCUGUGUUAGUCCUCUAUUGGUUUUUGUCAAUUCUAAGAGUGGAGAUAAUCAGGGAGUAAAGUUCCUCCGUCGCUUUAAACAGUUGCUAAAUCCGGCUCAGGUGUUUGAUUUAAUGAAUGGAGGUCCUCAUUUAGGUUUAAGAUUAUUUCAGAAGUUUGACAAUUUCCGGAUUCUUGUUUGUGGAGGCGAUGGAAGUGUAGGUUGGGUUUUGUCAGAAAUCGAUAAGCUCAACUUGAAUAAACAGUGUCAGCUGGGAGUGUUGCCUUUGGGUACAGGAAAUGACCUUGCCCGAGUUCUUGGCUGGGGAGGUUCAUAUGACGAUGACACCCAACUUCCUCAGAUCCUAGAGAAACUGGAACGAGCCAGUACCAAAAUGUUGGACAGGUGGAGUAUAAUGACAUAUGAACUCAAAUUGCCACCAAAAGCUUCCCUACUUCCAGGACCUCCAGAAGCAUCUGAAGAAUUUUAUAUGACGAUUUAUGAAGACUCAGUUGCAACGCAUCUUACAAAAAUCCUCAAUUCUGAUGAACAUGCAGUGGUCAUAUCUUCUGCCAAGACGCUAUGUGAAACUGUAAAGGACUUCGUUGCCAAAGUAGAAAAGACGUAUGACAAAACCUUGGAAAAUGCCGUUGUAGCUGAUGCCGUGGCCAGUAAAUGUUCAGUCCUAAACGAGAAGCUCGAACAACUGCUGCAGGCUUUGCACACAGAUUCCCAGGCUGCGCCUGUUCUCCCUGGCCUCAGCCCUCUCAUUGUGGAAGAAGAUGCUGUGGAAUCGUCCAGUGAAGAGUCCCUGGGUGAAAGCAAAGAGCAGCUUGGGGAUGACGUUACAAAACCUUCCUCCCAGAAAGCCGUCAAACCAAGGGAAAUCAUGUUGCGGGCAAAUAGUUUAAAGAAAGCAGUGAGGCAAGUCAUUGAGGAAGCCGGAAAAGUUAUGGAUGACCCGACAGUUCACCCCUGUGAACCAGCUAAUCAGUCCUCUGAUUAUGACAGCACAGAAACAGAUGAAUCUAAGGAGGAAGCUAAAGAUGAUGGUGCCAAAGAAUCAAUAACUGUUAAAACUGCACCUCGGUCUCCAGAUGCCCGGGCAAGUUAUGGCCAUUCCCAAACUGAUUCUGUCCCUGGUCCAGCUGUGGCAGCCAGCAAAGAAAACCUCCCUGUGCUCAAUACCAGAAUAAUCUGCCCAGGUUUAAGAGCAGGACUGGCUGCCUCAAUUGCUGGGAGUUCGAUUAUCAACAAAAUGUUACUGGCAAACAUUGAUCCUUUUGGUGCCACGCCGUUUAUUGACCCGGAUCUAGAUUCCGUAGAUGGAUAUUCAGAAAAAUGUGUCAUGAACAAUUACUUUGGGAUUGGAUUAGAUGCAAAAAUUUCAUUAGAAUUUAAUAAUAAAAGAGAGGAGCACCCUGAAAAAUGCAGGAGCCGAACUAAAAACUUGAUGUGGUAUGGAGUCCUUGGAACCCGGGAGUUAUUACAGAGAUCGUACAAGAAUUUAGAACAAAGGGUUCAACUUGAGUGUGAUGGGCAGUAUAUUCCUCUUCCCAGCUUGCAAGGCAUAGCCGUGUUGAACAUUCCCAGCUAUGCUGGAGGCACUAACUUUUGGGGUGGAACUAAAGAGGAUGAUAUAUUUGCUGCACCAUCCUUUGAUGACAAGAUCCUGGAAGUUGUAGCAAUAUUUGAUAGCAUGCAAAUGGCAGUUUCAAGGGUCAUUAAACUGCAGCAUCAUCGAAUAGCCCAGUGCCGUACAGUGAAAAUCACUAUAUUUGGUGACGAAGGAGUCCCAGUGCAAGUGGAUGGUGAAGCGUGGGUUCAGCCUCCAGGGAUUAUCAAAAUUGUGCACAAAAACAGAGCACAAAUGCUAACAAGGGACAGAGCCUUUGAGAGCACUCUGAAAUCUUGGGAAGAUAAGCAGAAGUGUGAUUCUGGUAAACCAGUUCUCCGAACCCAUUUGUACAUCCAUCACGCCAUUGACUUGGCAACAGAAGAGGUGUCGCAGAUGCAGCUAUGCUCCCAGGCUGCAGAGGAGCUCAUUACUAGGAUAUGUGACGCAGCCACAAUUCACUGUCUUUUGGAGCAAGAACUGGCCCAUGCUGUGAAUGCCUGCUCCCAUGCCCUGAAUAAAGCCAACCCAAGGUGCCCGGAGAGUCUUACAAGAGACACUGCCACUGAAAUAGCCAUCAAUGUGAAGGCGCUGUAUAAUGAAACAGAAUCUUUGCUAGUUGGCAGGGUUCCUUUGCAGCUGGAAUCGCCACAUGAAGAGCGAGUAUCCAAUGCCUUACACUCUGUGGAGGUGGAAUUACAGAAACUGACAGAGAUUCCUUGGCUUUAUUAUAUCUUACACCCAAAUGAGGAUGAGGAACCUCCUAUGGAUUGCACCAAAAGGAACAACAGAAGCACCGUAUUUCGAAUAGUGCCAAAGUUUAAAAAGGAAAAGGUUCAGAAGCAGAAGACAAGUUCACAGCCUGUUCAGAAAUGGGGCACAGAGGAAGUUGCUGCUUGGCUGGAUCUGCUCAAUUUGGGAGAGUACAAAGAUAUCUUCAUCCGUCAUGACAUCAGAGGGGCUGAACUUUUGCAUCUGGAAAGGCGAGAUCUUAAGGAUCUGGGGAUACCGAAAGUGGGUCAUGUGAAGCGAAUUCUCCAGGGAAUUAAAGAGCUUGGAAGGAGCACUCCACAGUCGGAGGUGUAAUCAUAUUGGUGCUAUUUCUUGGAAGAGAAGUUAUUGCCACUUAAUACAAAGUCCUUGGAAGCAAGUGGCUGUUCUUGUAGUUUUCUGCAUAGAUAAGUAAGCACCACUGAAGCACCUCUGUGGCUUGAUAUUUUGCUGUGGGUGAAAUUUUGAUUUGAGGUAUUAGAAAAUAUUUUUGUGCCGAACAAUACAUUCCACAAAGCCAUUUUCUUUUUGUGCAAACCUGACAUGUUCAAAUAUAUUCACAAUGGUAAUAAGGUAGGAGGAAUCUGAGACGAUUGCAUUGUCUAAACAGUGGAAUUGCAAAAUGUUUACUUUCCAUAGAUCUGGUCUGAUGGAAUGUUCCUACUGUGCAACUGCAUAACAAUAUGUGGUUAAAACUUCCUAGGUUUCAUUACGGGGGGGCAUUGGCCAUUUUCUUAAAAUCAUAGGUUAGGAGACUAAAAUAUAAAUUAAGUUGUGAUUUGAAUGUAGAUUGGUAUCACCUCCAACUCCUAGUGCUUAGUGGUCAAAUAUGUUGAAAACCUUUCCAAUACUAUGAAUGAAUGCAAAUCUUAAUGCACGAUGUUCCUGCCUGAAAUGUCUUUCUUUUUCUUGCAUGUCACAUCUAAUACUGUAACACUUUAAAUAGCUUUCAUGUCAGUUUUAAUGUUAAUGGGAUUUAAUUUAUUACUAAAGUACAUUUUUGUUGGUUAAGGGCACUGCACUUUUCUGUUUUUUAAUGUGGGAUUUUGCGUAAAUAUUCUGUACCUAAGACUUUGUGAAAGUGUGUCUGUGCCAUAAUCAACAAAUGAUAUACAUCACAUGCAAGUCAAUUUUAUUUCAAUCUAUCAUAAGCAGUAGGCGUGCACGUUAAGAAAAUUCUCUGGAUAUUUUCAUAAAAUUACAUGCUCCCUUACCUGACAAAACUUGUUACAGCUUUCCAAACCAAAAUUUCCACAUUUUGUUUCUAAUUUUUAAUUUCAAUUUAAUAAUUAUUUAAUAUUCUAUUUGAAUUUAUAAUAUAGUAAAGUGUUGAUAUCCAGGAAUUCCCUGAGGUGUCAACUGAGAUUUAUAUACUGACAGAUAACCCAGACUCACCCGCUCUCUACAGUGACUUCUGACACGAUCUUCCAAACAGAAGGGAUUUAAAUUUUUUCUUAAGGGCUUUAUGUUGUUAUUAUUAUUAUCUCACUUAAUUCUUAAUUCUUAUCAGGUGGAUAUUAUUUUCCUUUUUCUAAACCACUGUACUUCAGUGUAGCUUAUUAUUAGAAGUCAACAUUACAAUGAUCAAAUCUUUGAAAGCCAAAGGCAUACGUAUCAAAAAGUCACAAAAAUAUCCUUAAAUAAGCUUUCUUUAGCCAUUAUAUACCAAAACAUUAAUUAUAAUAUUUUAAAAUUUGUAUAUAAGAGAAAUAAACAGGGUACUGACUCAGUGGUGACAAUUUUUAUGAAGUAGCCUGCUAGGUGCUUAAUAGAUAUAUAUACACACAGAUAUAUACAUAUACACAUAUAUGUGUAUAUAUACAUACAUACACAUAUACAUUUAUAUGUGUAUAUAUAUACCUACAUACAUAUAACCUUGUGAUAUGGCAUCAUUGAUAUUUUCUAGACAAUUAUUUCCCCAGUGUUUAAAGAGAAAUACUAAUAGGCGAGCAUUUAAAAUGAACUAUUGUCAGGCAUAUUAUUUAAUUACAUCAAAGGAGUUUAACUGUUUGACACUUUACUCUUGUUUAUAACUUGGGUAUUUAACUACUAGUAAAAAUCACAAAAUUUUAAUGUCUUUAAAAUAAAUGACCCUGAGGGAUUCCUGACCAAGUAUGUCUGACUAUAUAUUUUACCUAAGUUGUAAAUAAAUGGAAAUUUUCCAAAGACAGUUAUAUCAAGUAGUUUAAAAAGUCAUGAGGCAGGGUGCUGUGGCUCACGCCUGUAAUCCCAGCACUUCGGGAGGUUUAGGUGGGUAGAUCACCGGAGGUCAGGAGUUCGAGACCAGCCUGACCAGUGUAUGAAACCCCAUCUCUACUAAAAAUACAAAAAUUAGCCGGGUGUGGUGGCACGCACCUGUAAUCCCAGCUACUCGGGAGGCUGAGGCAGGAGAAUUGCUUGAACCCAGGAGAUGGAGGUUGCAGUGACUGAGAUCACACCACUGCACUCUACUAGCCUGGGUGACAGAGCAAGACUCCCAUCUCAAUCUCAAAAAAAAAUAGUCAUGAAUUAUGCAAUUAUUCUAAUUGUAUCUGCACUUACGAAGUCAGAGGUCUCCUUUUUCAGUCCCUCUGAUAGUCCCACCUAAGUGCUGUCCUGCUCCUGUGAACACUUUCCUGUGCAACCAAACAGGAGGUGCCAGGUUCCCAGAACUCUCUAACAUUACAGAUCUCUGUCCAUCUUUACUAAAAAAAGGAAAUGUGAGGGAAAGAAGGGGAAGAACUCUAGCAUAAAUAAUGUAUUAAUAUAAAUAUCUAUAUUGAUUUUCACCCCCCAUUCCCCUUUGCUAAUAGAAAAGAGUCUAGCUAUGAUGUGUCCCAAAUUUAAGAGUGUGAUGUGAAGGACUGAAUUUUUGUUUGUUCGUUUGGUGAGCUUUUCACUCGUAGGUGACAUCUUUUGUAUAUGCUGUAAAGUCUCAGUUAAUGGAAUCCUACAGUGCAUUUCUGGCUAGCUCGGUUGGUAGAGCGUGAGUCUCUUAAUGGAAUCCUUAAUUAGCUAGAAUUUUCCUGCAAAUGGCUUUGGAUGAGGGAAAUUCUAUAAAAUGACAAUUUGGAUAUACUUUUUGUUAAAUGAGAGCAAUUUUCUCUGUAUGCUUUGUCUAUGCAUGGCUGUGCAGGGCCCAAAUGACUUCACUGACACCUGUUUCCAGGAGGGGGUCUUCAGAGCCUCCUUAGGCUCUUGUCAGUAUCAUAAAUAAUUCCUCUUCUUAUAGCGGAUGGGGUUACCAAAAAAAAUAAAAAGUAGGGAAGAGCUUCUCCAUGGGAUCAGAUCACAGCUUUGGGGAGUGGGAUGGGGCCUCUAUGCUUUGAUCUAUGCAUGAGCUGGGGUGAGAAGUUCCCACCUGCACCUGACUGCAAUGACUGUAAUGGCUGGAAUUGUCACCUCUUCUCCCUGAUAGGCUCUUCCUCACCUGGAGGAUCGGGGCUGGUGGGAGGGCAGGGAAGGGGAGGCCAUCAGCCAGAAUGUAUUUUCUUUCAGUUCCAUUUCCUGAGGAAGAACUUGCUUUUAAAGGAGGAAAGGGACAGAAUCAGACCUAAAUAAAAUUCCUGAGUAUGCAAUAUUUCUCUUUAGUGUCUCUUCACCUCCCUUUCUGAGUUUCUUUCCUACAUCCUGGCUCUUCAUUUUCCCAAUGCCCAAUAUAAUCAUGGUUGCUGAAAUUCUCACUGCCUUCUACUUUCCUUUCCCCAUCAAUUAACCCACUACAAAAUGACCCCUUUCAUUUCUCGCUUAAGCAUACAUGGUGGGUCAUUUAACUAAGUGUUAGGAAGAAAACAAUUUAAAGACACUAAUUUUACAGUUUGCGUUCUGUAAAAGGAUACUUGCUGGAUAAUCUAAGUGAAUUGAUGGAUUAGGUCAUUUGGGAUUGUGAUAUAUAUUGUUCUUGCUGACAAGAAAUGACCCAUGAAUGUCUAGAUCUAUCCUGUCCAAUAUUGUAGCUACAUGUGGCUAUCUAAAUUUAAAUGUAAUUUAAUUAAGCCAGGCAUAAUGGCACAAGCCUGUAAUUCCGGUGACUCAGGAGGCUUAGGAGGGAAGAUGGCUUCAGGCCAGGAGUUUGAGACCAGCCUCGGCAACAUAGUGAGACCCUGUCUCUGAAAAAAAAUUUUUUUAACUAGCUAGGCAUGGUGGCAUGCGCCUGUAGUCCCAGCUAUUCUGAAGGCUGAGGUGGGAGGAUUGCUUGAGACCAGGAGUUCAAGGCUGCAGUGAGCCAUGAUCAUGCUACUGCCCUCCAGCCUGGGCAGCAGAGCAAGACCCCUACUCUUUAAAAAAAUUAAUUUAAUUAGAAACUCCAUUUCUCAGUUGCACUAACUACAUUUCAAGUGUUCAGUAACCAUAGUGGACAGUGCAGAUGUAGAAAAUUUCCAUCACUGCAAAAAUUCUAUUGGACAGCACUGGUGCAGAUCAUUGCUACUCAAAAUGUGAUCCAUGGGCCAGCAGCAUCAAUAUUACCUGGGAGCUUACAGAAAUGCAGAAUUUCAGGCCCACUGCAGAUCUACCGAAUCAAAAUCUUCCUUUAGCAAAAUUUCUCAAACGAUUAGCACUGGCCUACAUCCAUUUUAUCCUUCCUUAGCUAUUAGGGAUGUGAGGUCCGAGGGCUUCAAAAGGUCCCCGGAAUAGCUUGUUCCUUCAUCCACUGUGUCCUAUUCAUUCUUCAGCUAACUCCAGCAAUGAGCUGAAACUCAUUCAUCACCCUUGCUGAGUUUUCUUCUCAAUCCUUAUUCCUAAUUCUGGUUCUAGAUGAGCCCUACCUACCCAGUGGUUGUAUUUUUGUAGCCAGUGUGGGACACAGGAGAUUGGCAGACCAACACAGCUAGCCUCUCUCUAGCCCUCCCUCCACCUCUAAGUCACUAACAAUCCAUGUUUGUUCAGUUUGUUGACAUGUGGCAUGUUCAUUUGUUCACAACUUAAUCACGGGGGACAUUUCAGAAAAAUGUGUACUAAGUUAAAACCAUGUUUAGUCUCCUACAACUUGUACAUUUUCAUUUUCUCUUAUCAGUAGAUUGUCCUUGUUGACAUAGCUCAUGCAUGAGGACACAUAGCAGUACACACACAUUGAAUGAAUUGUUAGUCAUGCAAAAAAAGAAAAGGAAUGAACCAAGAUGAUUGCAAGUUAAUCUCAUUUAAGCCCUCUAAAAAGGCAUGCUUUGCUAGAUUUAGAUCUGUUUUCCUUACACUCACUUAUCUUGAUGUUCACAUGGUUAAUAAUUCCUUAAAAUAGUGCCUGAAGAAUAAUAUUUCAUAUUCUUGACCCCCAAAUAACAGUUUACUUAAUUUUAUAAGAUUUUUCCCAAUGAGACUUAUUUUCAGGAAUCCUUCUCUUAAUAACUUUUACAUAUUGAUAUAAUGUACCAAAACACAAUUGCCUAGAGAUGCUUUAGCUAAUUUUUAUUAAUAAAGAGGACAAUAUUUUUGUCUUCAUGGAACUUAUUUUUAACAGGAAUCAAGGAAGAAAAUAUUCAUGCAGAGCUAUGACUUAGAAAGUUAUAGGGGCUGCCACUAUACAGCACUUCUAAAGUAAAACAUCUUCUAUCUCCAACUGGGCUGUCAACAUAGUGGACUUUCAUGUUCUAUGGAUAUGAAUUCUUUAAGGAUGUAGCCCUUAAUUAAGCUGUAAAAACAAUGCAUCUCUCAACCUUGACAUUUAGGAUCUCUCCUGUCUGCCCCCUCUACGCCCCACUCCAAUUAACUCAUCCUACAUCUCUCAGAUGUAAGUUGGAUAAGAGUGGGUUUGAAGUUUGGUAAUACAAGUGGCAGUUUUAAAACACCAAAUUCUUUAGAUCAGCUGAAAAGAAGAGUGAGAAUUGAAAAUUCCUCCACUAGUAAUUGUUAGCCAAUAGAAUAGCCUCCCAGAGCAGUCCCCACAGCACUUGGUUGCCAUGGGUUUCUCUCCUCUCACUGCCUGCCCCAGUGCCAUGAUGUCUGGGGCUUGUCUCUUCUAUGGCAUCCCCUGAUUGACUUUUGUAUAGCAACCUCUGUGUCAAGUCAGUAAUAUGAUGCCAUUGUAAUAGGAGGCCUUCCUAAAGAAGUAACUGCAACUUUUAAAACGUGAUGAUUAUUGGUUUUUAUAAUACACAAAGCAUUAAUUUUUUCUUAUCUUAUUUUCUCUUUAUUAUUUCUUUCCAACUUUUGUUUGGAGACAUUUAUGUUAGAAGAAAAACUAUAAAGUUUUAUCAUUGUAGAGAACAGAGAGAUCAAAGACAGCUGGACUGUACCUGUUUGUGUAAUUAUUUCUGAUAUUUUUAGGAAAAGAAGUUUAACAGAGUAACUCAGACUGAGACUGUUAAACUCUGUUCAUGAUAAACUCCAUAUUACAUAAUAUAGGUGAACAGAUUAAUUCCCUCCAUGUAACUAAGAUACUCUAUUUACAUUAUUUAUAUACUCUCUUAGUUUUUUAUGCACUUCCAAGUUUUAGUUGGAAAAAUGAAAACCAAGCUACUACUUAAAAGUUAUUAAAAACUUCACAUAAAAUAUUUCAUUUUAGCUACAAGUUAUUCAUUGCAUAGGAUUUUAUAAAUAGUCUGGGUAUUUCAUAGGAACUGCAUUUCAAAAGUGAAUUAACCAAACCUAAAAAAAGGGUUACUUUUAAAAUGCAUUAAAAUAAAGAAGUUUCAUAUUCAGUUGAUAAGGCCAUUAAGGUAGGAUAAUGCAGUUACAUAUACAAACUAAAAAAGGAAAAAGAAUAUAUUUUGUGGUCCUUAAUGUUUGAUUGCACUAUUGUUUCCCACAGCUUAGCCGUAUCUAUUUCUGUAUACCAAGUAUUAAGCUGAUAUGUAGCUAAAUAUUUCUUACAGUUCUGGUAACUGGUAACUAGUGCUGUGAAAGGUUUUGGUAUUGUAACAUUCCCAGUUUUGUGAGUUAUAUAUUGUAUAUUGAAGAUGACUAGUAAAUUCAAGUAAUAUAUUUAUCUACAGCUGGGAAAAUAUAAUUAUUUUCAAAUCUUCAAGUAAGUUGUAUCGAAUGUUUUUCUUCCUCUUAAGUGAGAUAAAUCUCACUUUUAUGUUAAAAUGUCUAUUUAUACAACAGGUUUCUCCUUUUGCUGUUAUUUUCAUAUUAAAAUUUUUCUUAUCUUUUUAUAUCAAAAUAAUUAUGCUGGCUAUUCAAACUGCCAAGAUGUAUUUUAGUUUGCAGGAUUUUUGGCAGACAAAAUAUUUAAUAACAAAUAUAAAAGCUUUGUAUAUUUUGUGGCAUUAGGGGCAAGAAUUUUACCUUUGGAUUUCUCUAUGUGAGGCAGUGCUGGUGUCAGCAAAGUCAGUAACAGACAGUAUUACUUGUAAUCAUCAAAAGAAGGUUUCCACAAGUUGUAUAAAUCAGUGCAUUUAUUUAUUAUGUUGUGAAACUUAAGCUUUAUAUGAAAUACAUAUUCUAGCUCUUUUCCUUUUUACUGCUGUUGUUUAGAGUGUGUAGUUCUGUUGAUGAUUUACUUAUGUACUUGAAGUACUCAUUUCUGUCAAACAGAUGCCCAACUAUUUUCCUUUUAAAAAACUGUAUUCUUUACUGCAAUAGAUAGCGGAAUAGUAAUAGACACUUUGUUAAAAAAAUAAGUUUCAUGUUUAAAAUAAAUAUUUUUUUAAAAUAUAAAGCCAAAAUGAAUUCACCAAUAUUAAGGAUUUAAUGUAGCCAAGGGAUUCAGUGUGUUAUAUUUUGCCAAUAUGUAUUUUAUCUUCAUGUCACAACUUAUUUUCUGUAGCCAAUUCUCAGUUUUAGUUGAAGAGAGAUCUCAGUGAUUGUACUGCCAAUAUGACAUUCAAAUGAACAUUAGGAAUCUUGAACCAUGGCUGAGCGCUGUUGCUCAGGCCUGUAAUCCCAGCACUUUGGAAAGCCGAGGGAGGUAGAUCACCUGAGGUCAGGAGUUUGAGACCAGCCUGGCCAACUUAAUACAAAAAUUAGCCAGGUGUGGUGGUGGGUGCCUGUAAUCCCAGCUACUCAGGAGGCUGAGGCAGGAGAAUUGCUUGAACCCAGGAGGUGGAGGUUGCAGUGAGCCAAGAUCUCGCCACUGCACUCCAGCCUGGGCGACAGAGCGAGACUCUGUCUCAGGGGGAAAAAAAAGAAUUUUGAACCCCCCAAAAUAUCACAUAUCUAGCAGUUCUAGGUUCCAGGGUGGAUAUUUUUAACAUAUGUUUGCAUUUGGUUCUGGGAUAGUAACCGUUAUGGAUAAUUGUUUGUUUCUGUCAAGUCGGUGAGAUUUUAAUUGUUUGAAUUAUUUCUAUUUAAAAUUACUCUCAAUUUAACUGUUUAAAAAACUAAAAAUUUAAAACAUAAUGGCACAACAUACGACACAGAAUAAAACACAUGUUUUCAAGGAAGAAGAAAAAACUGUUUUGACUUAAUGUGAAGCAGGGGUUUACCAAAGAAAAUUGCUUUAAUAAGCCCUAACUUUAACUGUUUUCUUCUAUGUUACAGUGUUAGCGGUUGAUGUAUUGUGUACUGUUUAAGAACUCAUAGGAGACUAAUAAUUAAUUUACUAUAAUUUUAAAGGCAAAGAGUUUUAUAUUAAUUUUACUGUUGCACAAGCAGUUAUUGGAAGUGGGGGAAAAAAAGAAAACUGGUGAGAGAAAUUACAUGGAAAUUAUAGGAAAAAGGAACUUGAAUUGGUAAUUUGGCAAAGAUUUGGGAACAAAUAGUUUGAACAUAGAUUUCUUUCACCUUAUAUGAUAGAAACACAAGGCACACGUGAGCUGUAUAGUGUGCUGAGCACACCCCCAGAAAACAAAAAAUAUCACAUUGAUGAAGUCCGAGACUGUAUCUAGAUCUUAGCAUAACUAGUGAAUUCAGGGAGCACAUCCUGCUGCUGAAAUUGAGAAGUCAGUAAGAAGGUAGUUCAGAUGACCUAAUCAUUCAAGACAUUUGAUGGAGUCCACACAAGGGUUUAUGAUGUGGGGCAAAUAUCUGUGCUUUCUCAUCUCAGUGAUUGAUGUCUGGAGAACUAGUCAGACACACUUAGCUGGUUCCUAUAGAAAAACACCAGUAAAUGUGGAUCAGACCAUACCCUGCAGACCAAGGAGAUUUUCUUAAACUUGCUAAGCCUUUCUUAAACUUGCCAAGUAUUAGCAAUGAUAAUUGCUAAAUGGAUUUUUUCCUUUCACUGAAACAACAAAACAAUUAUUGAAAUUCACAAUACCUAGAGAUGGGAACAUGGUUUAGGUUUAUCCAGUUCUGUAACUGACUUUGGCAUUGGCUCAUUGUGUCCUUUCUACAAGUUAUGUUUUGGUGACUUGGUGUCCCCAGUUAGAAAUGGCACACAAUAUUAUCAGUUGUUAGUACUUGGUAACGUUUCUUUUACUAAAGGAAUUAUAUAAGUAUGAAUCAUACCUAAUUUUACAAUUUCUUUCCCACGGUCAUUUUGGAUAUAAAGAUAGACUUCCCAGACAGUGAGGUUAGAAAUUAGAAGUUCAAAUUGAUAUCCCUGAUGUUUAAUUUAAAAAUGAAAGUAAAGUUAAAAUUAGUAGCAUUUGUACCAGAGUAGAUUAUGGGUAUUUUCAUCUGUUAUAUUACAUGUUCAUAUUAUUCAUUUUAGGAUAGGCCAAAACUCACUUCUAAAAUCUUCAAAAAUUUUGAAUAGUUUCAUUUUUUCAAUACUUAAGCCAAAUGACAAUUUUAUAGAUGUGAAUAUAUGUUUUUUAAAGUUAAGUCCUUCAUAUCUUUUCUUAGUUUAACUCCCCAAAGAGGAAAAUGUCUCUUUAAACCAGUAGUUAAAAAGAUGGAGUAUGUGAUGUUCCUUUCUCUGUACUGAGUUCUGAAUGUUUAAUCCAGAGCAUGGAUCACUGACUGCGUUCUCUGACUGUGGAAUGGUAUUCUUUCAUGCAAAGUACUUUCAAAACUUCCCAUAAAGAAACUAAACUAGAGAUUGUCUUUAUUAAUUAAUGGAACUCUGGGUAUGAUUAAGGGAAUUAAAUUAGAAAGUAGAAUAACCUAGUUAAAAUCAUUAUAUUAGUUAUACAUGAGAGUCAGUGAACGAUGACUUGAUUUUUACAUGACAUUUGAAUUCUGUCACUAUCUGAUUCUUGACCUAAAGGUUUCUUUGCUAAAUCUGAUAUUUAUUAUAGUAUAAUAUGAUAAUUUGGAGCUCCUGUUGCAUCUCACUGCCCCAAAAAUGUUGGAAUGCCAUAUGAUACAGGGAAAAGAUUGGAGUUCAUCACCGUGGAAUUUUGAUCUGUCUUAAUGACACAACUUAAUUUUCAUGAUGAUAGAUCUCUGAAUGAUUAAUCCAGAAUGAUUUGGUACAGUGACUGGAAGAAAUUGUUUUUCUGGGAAUUUGCUUCCCAUAAUGACCUGAUAUACAGGUGACCUUAGUAUAAUUGAAAUUAAUUAUAAUUUUAAUUAGAACAUGCUCUGUUUACAGAUUAUAAUUGCGCAGCAUUUUAAAAAAAUAUACAUAAUUAUGAGGAUGAGAGAAUUGCAAACUUGAACAGUUCUUUUGUUUUCUCUCCUUUUACUUGAAAAGCUUUCAGAAAGCUUUUGAAAGAUGACACAGUUUUCAUAGCAACAGUAUGCAAAUUAGGUUUUUCUGCCAAGAAACUCAUAAACUAAAGUAUGGAAUAACACAAAUGCUUAAUCUUAAUCUUGGCUUUGGAUUUUGUAAGCAAAAGCAUUUUCUGCAUCAAUUUUUUUCAGUAUGCAGUUGCAUAUUUCAUUUUUUGAUUAUGUCAAAAGUUGAAUUCUCAUUUUAUGCUGUGUUUCUCAUUAGUUGCAGUAAAGUGUUGAUUUCAUUGCUGCCUUUCAGGCCUUCAUCAUACAAACCCUCACCAUUUUUCACUCCUGUGCUUUUGCCAUAGGUUUUUUUUUGUUUUUGGUUUUUUUCCAGCAACUAGUUUUUCUACUUUCACUCUUUCCCACCAGAGUGGUCUCUCUAAAACAAAUUUGCUAAAGUUCUUAAGUAGGCUCUUUUUUCUCUAAAUUACAGAAUAGCAAACUAACUCCUAAGCAAGAUGAGUCAGUGUCUAUGACCUUGCCUCUUUCUUCCUUUUUAGUAUCCUCACCAACCUUCCCUCUGUUGACUUUUGUAAUCCAGGAAUUUGGAACUACUUAUGACUUAGUGCCUUGGCAUAAUCACAUGCCAUAGAUGAACAUGUUCAAGACUCAGUUCAAAUUUAACUUUCUGUGAAGCCCUACCUGACUUCCCUAGGCAGGUAUUUUCUCCAUGCCUAUAGUAUAUUGAAACUUUUUCUGUUAAAAUAACAUAACAUUUCAAUUACACACACACAACCUGUCUCUUCCACUGAACUUCUCUCUCCCCCUUUGUAUUCUCAGUGUCUAGCUACACAUAAUAGGACUUUGAUAAAUAUUUUUGAAUGAAGGUAAUAGAAAACCCGAACUUCUCUAUAUUUGUGUACUUUCACAAACAAAGGCUUAGAAUUCCACAUGAAAGUCCACAUGAGGUAAGUGUGCAUUCAUGAGCAUGUGUGCACUCUGGGCAAACCAACAGAAGAUAAACAGCAAGGAAGAGCAGUUGUUUUGUGAAAAAUAAUCAUCUGUUAGCUGUAAAUCAGAAAUAUUGGCCAAAUCAGAAUUCUUGUUUCUAAAAUGAGGCUUCUAAAAUUUUCACAUAACUGCCAAACUCUUAUUUGUAAUUCUUAAAUAUGCCCUAAAGAUCAUCUUUCUCUUUUAUAGACAUUUAGUGUAUACAGUCCACAUAAAUACAUAUACUGAUUACCUACAGACAAUAAUGAGACUUCAGAAAGAAUCAAAAGCAAUAGUGAUGGUGGAAUUUUUAAAUAAUAUUCAGCUGGGGGGAAAUAGACUGAGUUUGUGUGAUUUCAGGUUAUUUAGAGUUAUUAAUGUAAACAUAAGAAGGCUUGUGACUCUUAUCACCCUCUAUAGAAUAUAAAGACUAAAAAUAAAAACUAUUACCUCUGGGCCUGUUUUUCUUUGGGAUUAGAUAAAGCCUUUCUACCAUAUCACCAAAUACUCAUAAAGGCUAACACAGAAAGCUUUUCCAAGUUAAUAAUUUCUAAAAUUAAAUAUCAGGGCCAGGUGUGGUGGCUGACACCUGUAAUCCCAGCACUUUGGGAGGCCGAAGUGGGUGGAUUACCUGAGGUCAGGAGCUCGAGACAAGUCAACAUGGUGAAACCUCAUCUCUGCUAAAAAUACAAAAACUAGCCAGGCAUGGUGAUGCACACCUGUAAUCCCAGCUACUCGGGAGGCUGAGGCAGGAGAAUUGCUUGAACCCAGGAGGCGGAGGUUGCAGUGAGCUGAGAUUGCACCACUGCACUCCAGCCUGGGCGACAGAGUGAGACUCUGUCUCAAAAAAAAGAAAAAAAAUCAAAAUAAUUGUAAUUAACUGAAAUGCCCUGUUCCUUCAUUCACUUGAUAGACUUUUCUACCUGCUCUAUACUUGGCACUCAAUUAGAUUCUGGGGAUACAGAUAAAAUAAGACAAAGCUCCCAUCUGGUAGAGUCCAAGUUUGUUUUCACAGUUAUUUUUCCACAGUCUGUUUAAGGUAUUAGGAGGACUUUUAUAAACCGAGUGUUUUUCAGGUUACUUCAGAGAGGAGUCUCCUUCCACCCAAAAAAACUAACCAAAUUAUUUUAUCAUAAAGAGGUAAUCCCAUUUUUAUGUCCACAAUUUUUACAUUUUUGUAUCAGCCACCAAUAAUUUUGACUGUUUUGUCAAGUACAUAUUUCAUCAAUCCUAUUUCCACAGCCGUACAUGUGAUCCCAGUGACUGAUAGAUCUGUAGAAUGUGAACUCACAUUUAAAGUUUAUUUUGGGAAGGCAUAUAUGCCUUUUGAUGACACACACACCAAAAUAUAUAAGAGCUGUGCAUGGUAAACCCACAGUAGAAGGGAAAAAGUAAUGCUUUCUGGUAUACUUCAGAGGCUCCAUUUGAAGAUGUGCGUUGAUGUUUCCUUGAUUAUUUUGAAUGAGGAGUAGGCGGUAAUAUUUAACAGGUAGCAUACGUAUCUAAGCAUAUAGUAAAUAUUACUAGUACUUGUGUGCCAUGAGGCACUAAUACAUAGGUGAAACAAAAAUAUUUUUAGUUCUAAAAAAUUCUCUAGAUAUUUAUGGAUGGUUAGGCAAUAGGGUUCCUUCAUGAGAAGGAAAAAACUGUAUCUUUAUUGUCAGUAAGUGUGGAAAAAAACCCGACUUGUAUGUGUAUUCACAGUUUGAUAGGCAUAUUUUGAAGUCAUUGUUUUCCAUCAGUAUUAAGUAUCAUCCAUUUCUAUGUUCUCUAGCAAAAGAAAAUUCUUAGUGUGAUACAGCUUUACUCUUUGUUUGACUUUGUACAAGGUCCACAAAAGGAGGAGGCUCAAAAGAUUGGACACUUUACCCUGACAUUCAGCACAUUCAUUUUAUCUUUCGAUAAAGAUAACCAGAAAUCAUUUGCCUCUUGUUUAUUAUCAUGUUGAAAACACAACAGUAUAGUUCCUUUUGUCCCUUACAUUGGAAAAGGUAUUUUAAAUUUAGCCUUGCCGUAUUAUUUAUAGUUAGGAAUUUACUACAUUUUGGUAGUCUGUUUUGAAACUAAGCACUUGUGUCUGAAAGAUGCAGAUAAUAUCUAUCUAUUUAUUACACAGUGGGCUCUGUUUGCUGCAGAAAAGAGUGAAACUUUUAACUGCUUAGCACACUUGCCAGUGAAAUAUACCUGACAGAGCAGAGGUUAUAACUUUGGCUCUAAUUACUUUUAGUAAUGGUAAGACAACGUGAGUUUUGUUUGUUUACAUGCUGUUUACAAUGGCAUAAUUUUAAAAAUAUAUACAAUUGAGAUAUUUAUUGCCUACUAUUUUAAAGAUGUUUUAUGUGUUUUCACCUUUGGAAUAUAUUGUUACAUUUCCUUGUACAGAUAAUUUUGGUGGCUUUGUUAAUGUAGCUAGUAAUUUUUAUGACUACUAAGUGACCAGUUUUCGGUGCCUUUUAUUGUGGGAUGCAUGAUUAUGUAUUUAUUGUACGGAAGUCACUGACGUGUGUAUUUUUGUACUUUGCUGAAAGUAAUGGUUGAUCCUGAUGUACAUGAUGAUGAAAGACAUCUUUCCCAAAGGGCACUGCCUUGAGAUCAUCCUUCUCAAAUAAAAAGAAUGCAUUUGAAGAAA